AGACGCUACAGGAUGGAGCGGGGCGCAGGAGCCAAGCUGCUGCCGCUGCUGCUGCUUCUGCGGGCGACUGGUUUCACAUGUGCACAGACAGAUGGCCGGAACGGCUACACGGCGGUCAUCGAAGUGACCAGCGGGGGUCCCUGGGGCGACUGGGCCUGGCCUGAGAUGUGUCCCGAUGGAUUCUUCGCCAGCGGGUUCUCGCUCAAGGUGGAGCCUCCCCAAGGCAUUCCUGGCGACGACACUGCACUGAAUGGGAUCAGGCUGCACUGCGCGCGCGGGAACGUCCUAGGCAAUACGCACGUGGUAGAGUCCCAGUCUGGAAGGUGGGGCGCAGGGGUCGAGGAUCCCUUGGGGUGAUGCUGGGGCGAAUGGAGUGAGCCGCUGUGGUGUCGCGGCGGCGCCUACCUAGUGGCUUUCUCGCUUCGCGUGGAGGCACCCACGACCCUCGGUGACAACACAGCAGCGAACAACGUGCGCUUCCGCUGUUCAGACGGCGAGGAACUGCAGGGGCCUGGGCUGAGCUGGGGAGACUUUGGAGACUGGAGUGACCAUUGCCCCAAGGGCGCGUGCGGCCUGCAGACCAAGAUCCAGGGACCUAGAGGCCUCGGCGAUGACACUGCGCUGAACGACGCGCGCUUAUUCUGCUGCCGCAGUUGAACGGCGCCGCCGCCGCCGCUCUCUCCCGGGCCAGGAGGCUAGUCCCACCUCUUGCUAUUAAAGCUUCUCUGAGUUGA